AUGCGCACGAGCACCCCGCCGCCGCUGCCGCCGCCACCGCCGCCGCCGCCGCCGCCGCCGCGGCUUCAGCACCAGCGCCCGGACAGCGGUGCCGCCCACGGGCAUGGACGGUGACAGCAGCAGCAGCAGCGGCGGCAGCGGUCCGGCUCCCGGCCCGGGUCCGGAAGGGGAGCAACGGCCCGAGGGGGAGCCCUUGGCCCCAGACGGCGGCUCCCCGGACAGCACCCAGACCAAGGCUGUGCCCCCUGAGGCAAGCCCAGAGAGAAGCUGCUCCCUCCACAGCUGCCCCCUGGAGGACCCUUCCAGCUCUUCAGGACCCCCACCAACAACUUCCACCCUCCAGCCUGUGGGUCCAUCCAGCCCCUUGGCCCCUGCCCACUUCACCUAUCCCCGGGCACUGCAGGAAUACCAGGGGGGCAGUUCCCUGCCAGGACUUGGGGAUCGGGCAGCUCUCUGCUCCCACGGCUCCAGCCUCAGCCCUUCUCCAGCCCCCUCACAGCGCGAUGGGACCUGGAAGCCACCCGCUGUGCAGCACCAUGUGGUCAGCGUCAGGCAGGAACGAGCCUUCCAGAUGCCAAAGAGCUAUUCCCAGCUGAUUGCUGAGUGGCCAGUGGCCGUGCUGAUGCUGUGUCUGGCUGUCAUCUUCCUCUGCACCCUGGCUGGACUGUUGGGGGCCCGGCUGCCCGACUUCUCCAAGCCUUUGCUGGGCUUUGAGCCACGGGACACAGACAUUGGGAGCAAGUUAGUGGUCUGGAGAGCACUACAAGCCCUCACAGGCCCCAGGAAGCUGCUUUUCCUUUCCCCAGACCUUGAGCUGAACAGCUCGAGCUCCCACAACACUCUGAGGCCUGCACCCAGAGGCAGUGCCCAGGAGAGCGCUGUCCGGCCUCGGAGAAUGGUGGAGCCCCUGGAGGACAGAAGGCAAGAGAACUUCUUCUGUGGCCCCCCUGAGAAGAGCUAUGCAAAGCUGGUGUUCAUGUCCACCUCCUCGGGCAGCCUAUGGAACCUGCAUGCCAUCCAUUCCAUGUGUCGCAUGGAACAGGACCAGAUCCGCUCCCAUACCAGCUUCGGGGCUCUGUGCCAGCGGACAGCAGCCAACCAGUGCUGCCCCAGCUGGUCCCUGGGCAACUAUCUGGCUGUGCUCUCCAACCGCUCCUCCUGCCUGGACACUACCCAAGCUGACGCAGCCCGCACACUGGCCCUGCUUCGGACCUGUGCCCUCUACUACCACAGUGGCGCCUUGGUGCCCUCUUGUCUGGGACCUGGGCAGAACAAGUCCCCACGCUGUGCCCAGGUUCCCACCAAGUGCUCCCAGAGUAGUGCCAUCUACCAACUCCUGCACUUUCUGCUUGACAGGGACUUUCUGAGUCCCCAGACCACUGACUACCAGGUGCCUUCCCUCAAGUACAGCCUGCUCUUCCUGCCCACCCCAAAGGGUGCUUCCCUCAUGGACAUCUACCUGGACCGGCUGGCCACCCCCUGGGGGCUUGCUGACAACUACACCUCUGUCACUGGCAUGGACCUGGGCCUCAAGCAGGAGCUGCUGAGGCACUUCCUGGUCCAGGACACGGUGUACCCCUUGCUGGCUCUGGUUGCCAUCUUCUUCGGCAUGGCCCUGUACCUGCGCUCACUCUUCCUCACGCUCAUGGUGCUGCUGGGGGUGCUGGGCUCACUGCUGGUGGCCUUCUUCCUUUACCAGGUGGCCUUCCGCAUGGCCUACUUCCCCUUCGUCAAUCUGGCAGCCCUCCUCCUGCUGAGCAGCGUCUGCGCCAACCACACGCUCAUCUUCUUCGACCUGUGGCGCCUUAGCAAGAGCCAGCUGCCGUCGGGGGGGCUGGCGCAGCGCGUGGGCCGCACCAUGCACCACUUCGGCUACCUGCUGCUGGUCUCCGGCCUCACCACGAGCGCGGCCUUCUAUGCCAGCUACCUGAGCCGCCUGCCGGCCGUUCGCUGCCUCGCCCUCUUCAUGGGCACGGCUGUGCUGGUGCACCUGGCGCUCACGCUGGUCUGGCUGCCCGCCUCCGCCGUGCUCCACGAGCGCUACCUGGCGCGCGGCUGUGCGCGCCGGGCGCGGGGCCGGUGGGAGGGCAGCGCGCCCCGGCGGCUACUGCUGGCGCUGCACCGGCGGCUCCGCGGCCUGCGGAGGGCGGCGGCUGGCACCUCGCGUCUGCUCUUCCAGCGCCUGCUGCCCUGCGGCGUCAUCAAGUUCCGCUACAUCUGGAUCUGCUGGUUCGCAGCACUGGCGGCAGGGGGCGCCUACAUCGCCGGAGUCAGCCCCCGCCUGCGGCUGCCCACGCUGCCGCCGCCCGGCGGCCAGGUCUUCCGGCCCAGCCACCCCUUCGAGCGCUUCGACGCGGAGUAUCGCCAGCUGUUCCUGUUCGAGCAGCUGCCGCAGGGCGAGGGCGGCCACAUGCCCGUGGUUUUGGUGUGGGGCGUCCUGCCUGUGGACACUGGCGACCCUCUGGACCCUCGUAGCAACAGCAGCCUGGUGAGGGACCCUGCCUUCUCGGCCAGCGGCCCUGAGGCCCAGCGCUGGCUGCUGGCACUCUGUCACCGGGCCCGGAAUCAGAGCUUCUUCGACACCCUGCAGGAAGGCUGGCCCACGCUGUGUUUCGUGGAGACCCUCCAGCGCUGGAUGGAGAGCCCCAGCUGCGCCCGCCUGGGGCCUGACCUCUGCUGCGGCCACUCGGACUUCCCCUGGGCCCCCCAGUUUUUCCUGCACUGCCUGAAAAUGAUGGCUCUGGAGCAAGGCCCCGAUGGCACCCAGGACCUGGGACUCCGCUUUGAUGCCCAUGGCAGCCUGGCCGCCCUGGUCCUACAAUUCCAGACCAACUUCCGGAACAGUCCGGACUACAACCAGACCCAGCUCUUCUACAAUGAGGUCAGCCACUGGCUGGCAGCGGAGCUGGGCAUGGCACCUCCAGGCCUCCGCCGUGGUUGGUUCACUAGCCGUCUAGAGCUGUAUAGCCUGCAGCACAGCCUGAGCACUGAGCCUGCUGUGGUGCUGGGCCUGGCUUUGGCGCUGGCCUUUGCCACACUGCUCCUGGGCACCUGGAAUGUUCCCCUCAGCCUAUUCUCCGUGGCAGCUGUGGCAGGCACCGUGCUGCUCACUGUAGGACUCCUGGUUCUCCUCGAGUGGCAGCUCAACACUGCCGAGGCCCUGUUUCUCUCUGCCUCAGUGGGCCUCUCAGUAGACUUCACUGUCAACUACUGCAUCUCCUAUCACCUGUGCCCACACCCUGACCGCCUGAGCCGUGUGGCCUUCUCUCUGCGCCAGACCAGCUGCGCCACAGCCGUGGGGGCUGCAGCCCUGUUUGCGGCAGGCGUGCUCAUGCUGCCUGCCACAGUGCUGCUCUAUCGCAAGCUGGGCAUCAUCCUCAUGAUGGUCAAAUGCGUCAGUUGUGGCUUUGCCAGCUUCUUCUUCCAAUCUCUCUGCUGUUUCUUCGGGCCAGAGAAGAACUGUGGGCAGAUCCUCUGGCCCUGUGCCCACCUGCCAUGGGAUGCUGGUACUGGGGACCCUGGUGGGGAGAAGGCAGGCCGCCCACGACCAGGGUCAGUGGGAGGGAUGCCCGGGUCCUGCUCAGAGCAAUAUGAGCUACAGCCCCUGGCACGGCGUCGGAGCCCCAGCUUUGACACCAGCACAGCCACCAGCAAGCUGUCCCACCGGCCCUCAGUACUCUCUGAGGAUCUGCAGCUCCAUGAUGGUCCGUGCUGUUCCCGGCCCCCACCAGCCCCUGCCUCCCCAAGGGAGCUGCUGCUGGACCACCAGGCAGUCUUCAGCCAGUGCCCUGCCCUGCAGACCUCCUCCCCCUAUAAGCAGGCUGGCCCCAGCCCCAAAACCCGGGCCAGGCAGGACUCCCAAGGGGAGGAGGCUGAGCCCCUGCCAGCCUCACCAGAAGCCCCAGCCCACUCUCCUAAGGCCAAGGCUGCAGAUCCUCCUGAUGGCUUCUGUUCCUCAGCCAGCACCCUGGAGGGGCUCAGCGUCUCUGAUGAGACCUGCCUAAGCACCUCUGAGCCCAGUGCCCGUGUACCAGAUUCCGUGGGUGUGUCCCCAGAUGACCUGGAUGACACUGGGCAGCCAGUCCUUGAGCGAGGCCAGCUCAAUGGGAAGCGGGACACCCUGUGGCUGGCGCUGAGGGAGACAGUGUAUGACCCAUCAUUGCCCGCUUCCCAUCACAGCAGCUUGUCCUGGAAGGGCCGAGGGGGGCCAGGGGAUGGCAGCCCUGUGGUGCUGCCCAAUAGCCAGCCAGACCUGCCAGAUGUUUGGCUGCGCAGGCCCAGCACUCACACGUCAGGCUAUAGCAGCUGAGGGGGACCCGGGGAGGCUGGACAGGGCGCGGAACCCUGUCAUGGAUGACAAGGCAAGGGCAGCAAUAGGCUGGAGCCCGAAGGUAUUUCUCCAGAUCCACAGGGAGAGGUCUCACCCUCCAGCUGUGGAUGUUAAACCCUGCCAGAUGUCCCAGCCUUGAUCUGUCUGCUCCUACUCCUCACAUCUGGAGGAUUCCAGCAGGAGGGGUUUUGGAGGGGACCUGCUUGCGACCUGCUGAGGGCUUGUCUGCUCCCACAGCACCAUCUAAGACCCCUCCUCUAGAAGUGGGGAAGGCCAGAUGUGUAGCUUCGGGUAUCAGAGGAGGCUGACCUGGCCCCCAUCCCAAGUUACAAGAACUUCAGUGAGACUAAGGGACCCCCAUCCUAGGGAUCUUGUCAGGGUUCCUUACUGACCAGAGGAGCCCGCAGCAAUCUCCACAGCCUCCUGGGUCUCACCCCUUUCAUGGGCUCUUCAUCAGGACACUUCCCUCUCUUUUGGGAGCUUCUCUGGGCAGAAUUGGGCUGGGACCUCUCUCCCCAACUGCCCUGCUCUCCUCAUACUCACCGGUUUGACCAGAAAUUCUCCAAAUCCAGCCAUAGAUGGCUGCUGGGUGUGCAGCAGGAGAAGGAGGAUGGUCAGCCUUGGAGCAUCUCUCAAUUACGGGACAGUCCCUCUUUGGAAGCAGGCUCCUGUGCUUUCCUGUGUUAAUAAACAGUAAUAAUCCUUUCCAUCUCUGCACAUUUUAGUCUCCUUGGAAUCUAUCUCACUACUUCACUACAGGGUAGCCUGACAUUGGUCAGGUUCUUUUGACACCCAAUUUAUAGGUAAAGACAUUGAGACUAAGUAAGAUGAACUGACCUCAGGGUCACUUAGCCACUAAAUGGCAGAGCGGUUUCAUUCCACCACUACAACCUCCAGUUUCCCUUUGGCUACCUGCCUUCUUUCACCGCUAGCACCCUCCUCCAAUCUGCUUUCUCUGGUGUCUCUGACUGAAUCCAGCCACCCUCUUUGGGCCUCCACUUCCUGAGAGAGCUGUAUUCCAAAAAAACCCAGGAGUUCCUCUCCAUCUCCCCCGUGCCUCCCUCUGGAAUCUGGCUGAGAUGUCUGCUGGCCCUGGGGCGUCCUAGCUGACCUGAUUCCCAGGCUUCAGGACCGUGCCUCUUCUACAGCCACAGUGUAUAAGAGGCCCCACCAGAAGAGGUACUGAGGGGCAGAAGAGGUGAAGCCAAAUCCAAUCAAGGCAGGAACUCAGACCUGCCCUUUGGGAAGUGUAUGAGUCUGAAGCUGCUUCCCAGGUUAGGGUCCCCAGCUUUUUAAGGACAAGUCUCUCUGUGGAGCGUUAAGCAGACCAAAGGCUGGUUCCUCCUUCCCAAACUUCCUGGUAGGGAAGUUUUAUCCCAUGUGAGAGCUCAUGACACCAGGUGGCAUCAACAUGUUUAUUGAACACCUACUUUGCAUAUGGUAUUACAAGGGGACAGAGGUGUGGAAGAAAAAUUGAACACCACCCUCAAAGAGCUCACCUUCUAGCUGGGGAGACAGCUUAUGCACACAUGCAGGCAUCGGAUGGCUCACGGACGGCACCAUAUGCCUGCCAUCAUCAUUAUUGUUGGAGCUCAAGUACCCAGGACUGGGUAACAAGAAAGGCUUUCUGGAGGAGGAAAAACUUGAGCUGGGCUUCAGAAGACCAAGCGUCUCAGACUGGAAGGGGCCUUGGCGAUCGUUUAUUCCAGCAGUUUUCAAAUUUUGUAGCCUCAGGACUCUUUCUUCAAAGAAGCUCUGUGUGGAAAAACAAUAUAUAAAACAGGUAAAAGGCAGCUACUCUGGUGGGCGCUGGGUGUUGGGGGUGGAGUCAGCUUAGCCUGUCUUUCCACUGCAGCCUCUCCGGGUAUCUGGGGAACCCCUCCGGCUCCUGGCAGCUUCACAGAAUGUAAUAUGAAAGCUACUGAUCCAGGCUAUUUUACAGAGGAGUAUCAGGAAAGGGAAGGGAUUGUUCUAGGGCCAAAUAGUCUGUGGCAGAGCUGGAGGCAAAUCAGAUGAUGUUUUUGUUUUAUUUAGUUUUUUAUUAUUGAGACCUACUUCCUACUCCAAGUAGCCCAUGAGAAGUGGAGCAGAAACCGAAAAGAGACAUGGGAGUUGUGGAAGAGACAGAAGGCAAUAGGCAGGUACGGCAGGAUACCUUGGCUCCUUUGCAAGAUAAGUAAAUCAAGAUGAGUAACUCCUGACACCAGGAAGGGGAAGCUGGAACCUAAUUUGAACCUGUCCCCAGGGGGUCUGCUGGGACCUCUCUCUUCAUGUCCAGGUAGCAUUCGGCCUCUCUGACCUAGAGCUGCUCAUCAGCCCUGGUUUCUCUGAUAAUGGUGUCCCUCUGUCAUCAUGCAGCCAGGCUGAGAGAGCCCUGGUAUCCUCAGGGACAAUGAGCCACAGGGAGGUUAAGGGAACUCUUCCUCCCAAGCAUGAGCAGAAGACACUUUGCCUGAACAUAACCACUGAAAUGUUAGAAUGCAGAGGGGUGGAUGGGUGGGCAUGAGGGAUCUGAGCACACCCGAGGGCCCUACCUGGGGAUUUCCAGGUCAUAUUCUUGCAGGCUGUGGCCACACAACACUUCAGGAAGGUGAAUGAGCCAUAGCAGCUGAUGCAUUGAUUAGAUUUGUUCUUUAUGUUGCCAGGCCCAGAAGAACCCAGCAGUAAUCUAAAACAUUACCUUAUACCUAGAAUGGCCCAAACCAACAGCAGGCAAUCCACAUCAGCAGGAAAUCCAGCCUGCCUCUCUAGCCCUGACUUUGGAAUGUGGAACUUAAAGCACUUCCUAUUUCCUUUGAGUUGCAGCAGAUCCUUUGCUUUAUUAUUAUUAGGGGCACUUACAAUGAGUGUAUGGCCCUGGAGACAUGGCUUACAAGCACGCUGUGAGGCGUACAAAAAUGAGUCAAAGCACUUAUGCUUGCCCUGCAAAAUUCAAGAAAUGAUUUCUCCCCACUCAGACACUCUAAUAGAACUACAUUAACAUUUGGAACUUGAGGUCAUUUCCCCUAUUUGUGCCACUGAUCCUUGAACUCACAUUCUGAGUACGAGUAUGUAUCCUGUAUGCUAUUAAAAUAUAACUUGAGGCCGGACAUGAUGGCUCAUGCCUGUAAUCCCAGCACUUUGGGAGGCUGAGGCAGGUGGAUCACUAGACGUUAGGAGUUUGAGACCAGCCUGGCCAACAUGGUGAAACCCCGCCUCUACUAAAAAUACAAAAAUUAGUUGGGCGUGGUGGGGGAUGCCUGUAGUCCUAGCUACCCAGGAGGCUGAGGCAGGAAAAUCAUUUGAACCCGGGAUGCAGAGGUUGAAGUGAGCCGAGAUCGUGCCACUGCACUCCAGCCUGGAUGACAGAGCAAGACACCGUCUCAAAAAAUAAAUAAAUAAAUAAGUCGGGCACGGUGGCUCACGCCUGUAAUCCCAGCACUUUGGGAGGCCAAGGCAGGUGGAUCAUGAGGUCAGGAGAUCGAAACCAUCCUGGCUAACAUGGUGAAACCCCGUCUCUACUAAAAAUACAAAAAUUAGCCGGGUGUGGUGGCGGGCGCCUGUAGUCCCAGCUACUCGGGAGGCUGAGGCAGGAGAAUGAUGUGAACCCAGGAGGCAGAGCUUGCAGUAAGCCGAGAUUGCGCCACUGCACUCCAGCCUGGGCAACAGAGCGAGACUCCAUCUUAAAAAAAAAAAAUAUAUAUAUAUAUAUAUGUAAACUUGAUAUAGUCUGUUACCAUGGGAAAACCAUCCUUCCAUGGCUGUGGUGAUUUGGGGACUUUUAGAGUGACAGUGUUAGACAGACUGAUUUUAUUGGCUGAAUCUUAGAUUUUACUGAUAUAUAGCAUAUCCCAUACCAUGAUAUGCGGGCAAUAUUCCAGCUUGAGACAAUUUUUUUUUUUUUUUUUUGAGACAGAGUCUUGCUCUGUCGCCCAGGCUGGAGUGCAGUGGCACAAUUUCGGCUCACUGCACUAAUUUUUUGUAUUUUUAGUAGAGACAGUAGAGUAUUUUUAGUGUUAGCCAGGAUGGUCUCGAUCUCCUGACCUCAUGAUCCGCCUGCCUCGGCCUCCCAGAGUGCUGGGAUUACAGGCAUGAGCCACCGCGCCUGGCCGAGACAAUUUUUAAAAAGACAUUUCUCAAGAGAGUUAUAAGCCAAAAUUUCCCUAGCCCCCUCCAACUCAUUCUGUCCUUCUCCCAGUGCAUGUCAGGACAGGGAAGAAGGCUUUAAAUCAGAUUUUAAGAAAGAGGAUACAUUGGUUUACAACCUUUGCCUAUCGUCCAGAGAGUUUCUGAUCUUUUCUUUUUUUUUGAGACGGAGUCUUGCUCUGUCGCCCAGGCUGGAGUGUAGUGGCACGAUCUUGGCUCACUGCAAGCUCUGCCUCCCAGGUUCACGCCAUUCUCCUGCCCCAGCCUCCCGAGCAGUUGGGACUACAGGCACCUGCCACCACGCCUGGCAAAUUUUUUGUAUUUUUAGUAAAGACGGGGUUUCAUUGUGUUAGCCAGGAUGGUUUCGAUCUCCUGACCUUGUGAUCCGCCCACCUCGGCCUCCCAGAGUGCUGGGAUUACAGGUGUGAGCCACUACACCCGGCCCUGAUCUUUUCUUUGACGGUGGCAGUAUCUCAUUUUUUGAUAAUACACAUGGGUAAUGGCAAGCUCUUGGGACCCCAUGCCAAGCAUCAAGAUCCCAUUUACCUGGUGAUAGGAAAGACAGACAUUCCUCACCCUUUCUACCCACACCCUUGUUCACAGGGAUGACUGUAACUAAGGUCUGCAGGUAUUUAUGCUUAGGAGAAGAAAUCGUAGUUCAAUUCACCAGGAAUAUGAGAAACAAAAGAAAGCCACUAUGUGCUAUGUAAAUGUCUGGCCAUCCAAAGCCACCUUAUGCAGAGGAACACUGGAAGGGCCUUGAUAAAUUUCUCAUAAUUAUUAUCGGGCCUCUUUGUGAUUACUCACAUUUUUCUCAAUAUAGGGGAAAGAUCAGCAUUUUACCAAAUCCACAACCAUCAAACAAACAAGAGCUUUAAUAUUGCUAAAGAAAAUCACACAGCUGAGCAGAUUGAUGUAGAUUUGAAUUCAUGACCACCUAUCUUAACUGGACCCUCAGCUCUGCCUAGCUAGUAUUCAUUCUAGCUACUAGUUUUGAUUAUUUGUAUUGACUCUUUUAUAUUUUCUCCACCUUCCUCAAAUAUCUCACCUUCCCCCACCCCUCAGUGGACAAAAAAAAAAAAAAAAUUCUUCAUGAAGAAAACUGAAGCCUUCAAAUAGAAAUUUCCUCACCUUCAAGGCACCAAAGCCACAACUUACCUACCCCCGCUCCUGCCUGCUCCUCUCCCCAUCCCUUCUGCUACAACGAAGGAAGCAGUAAUGGCUCCAUCAAUGGCUUCUCACACUUGGUGUCAGAGGCCUUCACACGAGGGUUUGCACUCCCCUACAAGGACAUGAAGACUUUCUAGAAGGUAGGUGGACACAGAUAGUUUUAAAGUAAUCAGUUUCCAGAGCCGCCUUCUCCAUAUGUUCCCCUCCUUAUAUUGGUGGGCCUAAGAAGCCACAGGCCUGACAGCUGUCCUUCCCAACUUCCACUUUCCCAGUUGCCUCCCCUCCCUCAUUCUGAAUCCUACUCUGGCUCCUUGCUCUGCGCUGUAAAAAACAAAUAAAAGGGCCACUUGAGAAUGCUCUGCUUGAGGAAGUCCUUGAAAGAGCAAAGCCUGGAGAGCUUCUUUGAGAAAGUUCACAGGGGCAGCCCUGUGGCUCAGUUCUGUGCCUUCUUCAUUUAAGAAUUCAAAUUCAUUGACAUGUUAUAUUGUAAAAUAUAUAAAUAUAUAUUAAAAAGGAAAAAAUAAUAAAAAUUUUUAAAAAUAAUUCAACUUCAGGUGAGACACAGUGGCUCAUGCCUAUAAUCCCAGUGUUUUGAAAGGCUGAAGUGGGAGGAUGGCUUGAGGCCAGGAGUUUGAGACCAGCUUGGGCAACAUAGCAAGAUCCCGUAUCUACAAAAAAUAAUUUUAAAAAUUAGCUGGGCAUGGGCCGGGCGCGGUGGCUCACGCCUGUAAUCCCAGCACUCUGGGAGGCCGAGGCAGGUAGAUCAUCUGAGGUCAGGAGUUCAACACCAGCCUGGCCAACAUGGCAAAACCCUGUCUCUACUAAAAAUACAAAAAUUAGCCGGGCGUGGUGGAGCAUGCCUGUAGUCCCAGCUACUCAGGAGGCUGAGGAAGGACAAUCGCUUGAACCCUGGAGGCAGAGGUUGCAGUGAGCCAAGAUCAUGCCAUUGCACUCCAGCCUGGGUGACAGAGCGAGACUACAUCUCAAAAUAAAUAAAUAAAUAAUAAAAUAAAAAUAAAAAUUAGCUGGGCAUGGUGAUAUGCGCCUGUAGACCCAGCUACUCCAGAGGCUGAAGCAAGAGGAUCACUUGAACUCUGGAGUUCGAGGUUACAGUGAGCCAUAAUCACAUUAUGGCACUCCAGCCUGGCAACAGAGCGAGACCUUAACUCUAAAAAAAGAAAUAAAGAAGAAUUUAAACUGAAAGUGAGAUGGUUGACACAGGAUACAUAUUAACCACAUUGAUUUGAAUGGAAAAAUAAAAUCAGACUUUUUCUGUUAGAAGGUCAGAAUUGGCUCACAGGUUUGACAGAGAGGAUAGUCUUUGCAAGUAGGAUGUAUGGUGGACAUUUUCCCUAAAAUGGAAUAACUUUAAUCUGCAGCUCCACAGUUUGAACAAAAACAGACUGAAGGCUGGGCGUGGUGGCUCAUGCCUGUAAUCCCAACACUUUGGGAGGCCUAGGCGGGCAGAUCACGAGGUCAGGAGAUCGAGACCAUCCUGGCUAACAUGGUGAAACCUCAUCUCUACUAAAAAUACAAAAAAAUAGCUGGGCGUGGUGGCGGGCACCUGUAGUCCCAGCUACUCAGGAGGCUGAGGCAGGCGAAUGGCGUGAACCCGGGAGGCGGAGCUUGCAGUGAGCCGAGAUUGCGCCACUGCACUCCAUCCUGGGCAACAGAGUCUCAAAAAAAAAAAAAAAAAUUUUUGACUGAAAGUACAGAUACAACUUCCCUUUCCAGCCAAGAUGGAGGAGCAGGGGCCAAGUUUAUCCUCCUGCCUGAAACAACCAACCAAACAGUAAAUACAUGAAAUAAUGAGUUUCAAGACACUGGACAUGAGGUAACAAAAGACAGUGAUCUCUCAGAGGCAAGAAACAAACAAGGAGAACCCCUCGGUUGCCCAGCUUACCGCUUGAGAGGAUGUAUUUCACGGAGGGAGAACCCAGGCAAAGCAAGUGACUCUGAGGUGAGGGGAUAGCUGGGAGUGUGGAGCAGCCAAGCUGGCUAGAGUGCUCAGGACAGGGUACUGGAGAGGAGAAAGGUGGAUAUAUAGAGAAUUCUGGGGAUCUGCAAAGGGCCCCCCUUGAGUGUUCCACAGAGCAUGAUUCAUCAUAUAAGUGUAAGGAAACCACUUGAGACAAAGGAAAGGACCACCCAAAACAAUGGGCCGGAACAGUAGCCAGAAGUCACACACAGCCUGGACCACGCCUGUCCCCAUCAGCCAGAUUGGAAAACCUCAAAUUUAUGGAGCAUUGGUCAGAGGUCUCAGAAGGGCCUUGCCUCGUAGUGGGGAUUCAUUAGCCCUAGUUUAAACAUUGCUGGAACCUACCUAACAAAUCUCAAAAGCAAGACCUGAAUUCAGGAAUCAAGCUGUUUCUAAGUAACUGAAGUGUAUCCCAGAACAAAACCCAAGAACAUUAACAGAAAUCCAAAAUUAACGAGCACCCAAAAAUGUAAAAUUCACAAUGGCUGGUUUUCCAAUAAAAAAUUACCAGUCAUGCAAACUAUAACCCAUCAUAAGGAGAAAAAUCAGUUGAAACCACUACAGCUGACACCUAUGUGAGAAUUAGACAAGGACACUAAAAGAAUUAUUAUAACUGUAUUCCAUAUGUACUAAGUAGAGACUAGGAAGAUAUUUUUAAAUACCCACUUUGAAUUUUAGAGACGAAAACUAAAAUGUCUGAGAUGAUGGGGUGGGUGGGGUAGGCAGAAAGAGGAGGAUGGGAAGAAGUACCAAGGGGAAGGAGGAAUGAUUUGGGGAUGACGGCUGUGUUUAUUAUCUUAAUUGUGGUGAUGGUUUCACAGGUAUAUGUAAUUUCUAAACUUAUCAAAUUGUACACUUAAAAUAUGUGGUCUAUGGAAUGUUAAUUAUAUCUCAAUAAAGCUGUUAAAAUUGUACUGAAACAAAACCAUUGGGGGAAACUGGGUAAAGAGUCCAAAGGACCUCCCUAUACUAUCAUUGUAACUUCCUGUCAAUUAUAACGAUUCCAAAA